AUGUGCGGUGAGGCUCGCGGCCGGAGUGCGGCGCUGGGCGGAAGCUACCAUGGCGGCCGAGCGAAAGACAAGGUUGUCCAAGAAUCUACUGCGCAUGAAGAAAUACAGGUAUUCAUGCUAGUGAGAGACUGGCAGCAGGACUGUUAUUUACUGCCAUAUUUUGAGUCAACUUUCUGCAGAUUUGAUAAGAGCAGCUCAAGAGUUUAGCAGCAUUUCAGAGGAAAAAUAAAAACGAAGAGCAGACUUAUAGAUGUACCUUUGCUUCUGCCUACAUUUAUCGGGCUCUUACUGUGCUUCAGUCAUCAUAUUGGGACAGAUGAAGGAGAUGACCCAGACACCCAGUCCUUAAGGUCUCCAGAAAAGAUAGAUGCUCAGAAAGUUCAGAUGUGUUUAUGCAAAGGGGACUGGACUCAGAAACCAAGAAACAACUAGAAGAAGAAGAAAAGAAAAUCAUUAGUGAAGAGCACUGGUACUUGGAUUUGCCAGAGCUUAAAGAGAAAGAGAGUUUCAUAAUAGAAGAGCAGAGUUUCUUACUAUGUGAAGAUCUUCUCUAUGGAAGAAUGUCAUUCAGAGGAUUUAAUCCUGAGGUUGAGAAAUUGAUGCUUCAGAUGAAUGCUAAGCACAAAGCAGAAGAAGUUGAAGAUGAAACAGUAGAGCUUGAUGUGUCAGAUGAAGAGAUGGCUAGAAGAUAUGAGACCUUGGUGGGGACAAUUGGGAAAAAGUUUGCCAGAAAGAGAGACCAUGCCAAUUAUGAAGAAGAUGAAAAUGGAGACAUAACACCAAUUAAAGCAAAGAAGAUGUUCUUAAAGCCCCAGGAUUAAGAUGGAUGCCUUAAGCGAUGGCCCAGGGGUGCUUGGUGGAAGUCAGCAGGGCAUCUGGAGCUCAUCCCAAUGGUGUCUCUAUAGUUAUUAAUACUGUAACGUUUACUUGUAAAGAGAUUAUCAUUUUAGAAACAUGCUGUUUUUGAAACAGAUGUGUGAUGGAUGUUGUACAUCCUUUGCUUCUUGGUAUUCAUUCAGAGUGGAUUUUUAGCCCCUGAUCUACAAAUGUACAUUGUUACAGGGCUGCUUCCUAAAGAUUUUUUUUACCUCAGGUUUCUCUUAAUAUAGUUCUCCAGUCACUGACCUUGAAUUGACUUACAUAAACUACUGCCAAUGUUUAAAUUGCCCUUAUGUUUAUAUUUAUUAUGUCAAGCCAAUUCGUACAUACAAUUUGGAAUCAAAUGUCAUAAGAAUUUAUUAUAUAAAUUUAUCAAGAAUAAAAAUGCCUCUCCAGCCUUAAGUAUUUACAUGCUCCCAGGUCAUUGUCAGUUUAUGGUAUUAUGUUGUUUUAUUUAAAGCAUUGAAUUGAUAGAAAAAUUUGCUCUGUAAUAAAAAUCUACUUUCACAUA